CUUCCGGUGGCGGAGCGGCGGAUUAGCCUUCGCGGGGCAAAAUGGAGCUCGAGGCCAUGAGCAGAUAUACCAGCCCAGUGAACCCAGCUGUCUUCCCCCAUCUGACCGUGGUGCUUUUGGCCAUUGGCAUGUUCUUCACCGCCUGGUUCUUCGUUUACGAGGUCACCUCUACCAAGUACACUCGUGAUAUCUAUAAAGAGCUCCUCAUCUCCUUAGUGGCCUCACUCUUCAUGGGCUUUGGAGUCCUCUUCCUGCUGCUCUGGGUUGGCAUCUACGUGUGAGCACCCAAGGGUAACAACCAGAUGGCUUCACUGAAACCUGCUUUUGUAAAUUACUUUUUUUUACUGUUGCUGGAAGUGUCCCACCUGCUGCUCAUAAUAAAUGCAGAUGUAUAGCAGUCCUGUCUGGGGCCCAUUCUGCAGGGGUGGUGGGUGCUGGGACCUACAUUGCUUCCCCAAUCUCUUCCCUUUCCCAUUUCUCAUCUGCCUUUCACAGUUCCUGCUGCUGAUCUACUUAAGGGGGAUGAGAUUUGUGUAGCACCGGUGUUUUGUCAUUGGAAUUUAAGGCUUACCUGUGGA